AGUUAGUAGUUGGUCCCAGUCAGUAACACUCUGGGAGGGCUCAGGCCACAUCACGAAAUGUGACAGGAUAGCCUUGAACUCAUCAAUUGCUGGGGGCACCUCAAACUCAACUCCAAAAUUGAUCUAAUGAACUUUCCCAAACCACAUUCCCUUCUUGCAUUUCUGAGAGAAUGGAUUCCCAUUCAUCUGACUACAGUGCUACCCUGAAAGCAGAUCCAGAGACUAAGAUUCACCUGCAGGUGAUUCAUUUGCAAGGUAAGCUGUCAUCAGUUGGAGGUAAGCGGAAGACAGUAGAGAGUACAGAGCCCUGGACUGUGACUCAGAGGAUGAGCACCAGAUCCAGUUUGCUGUGCCACAGUGUCCUGAAGAUUUUCCUCAGAUAAUCUUUCAUCUCUUUGUUCCUGAGACUAUAUAUUAGAGGAUUACAGAGUGGUGUUAUCACAGAAUAGAACAAGUGGAUUUUUAUCUGAGAUCUACAACUUAUGAAGAAUACAAAUGAUGUAUAUUCUUUUCUACUCUUCAUGUAUGGACUAGAGGGGCUUGCACAGUAGUAAGAAAAAAAUGGCUGAGACCCACAGGAACAAAGAAACAGGACAGGAGUUAGAUGCAGAGAAGAGAUUUCAACAAAAGUUUGGAAGAGAUGCUAACGGUAGCAUCUGAGUCACAGACAGAACAUUGGCACCUUUGUUUAAGAAACUGAAUGUUAAUGUCACAUCUGCCUUUGGAGAUUACAAAUGAAAUGGCUACCUUUCUACUGGAACCCUGACCAGAAGUCUGCCAGUUAGUAAGCUGGCUUAAGAGAUCAAUCUAAAAUUUACAUAAGGCUUUUGAAAAAAAGAAAAAAGAACCCAAAGGCACAGAUUGACGUUAUAAGUCCUGAUUUUUGACUUGACUUCUCAUCACCUGGAAGUGAAUAAAGCAGUAGACUUCUCUAACAUUUUGUAACACAGCAUGAAAAAAUAUAGAGUACAAAAGAUAUAUAUAUAUAAUAUGAUAAAAUGAUGAGCAGAAGAAAUGAAGAUAGCAAACAACACAGUAGUGACAGAAUUUAUCCUCCUUGGUCUGACUCAGUCUCAAGAUAUUCAGCUCUUGGUCUUUGUGCUGAUCUUAAUUUUCUACCUUAUCAUCCUCCCUGGAAAUUUUCUCAUUAUUUUCACCAUAAGGUCAGACCCUGGGCUCACAGCCCCCCUCUAUUUCUUUCUGGGCAACUUGGCCUUCCUGGAUGCAUCCUACUCCUUCAUUGUGGCUCCCAGGAUGUUGGUGGACUUCUUCUCUGAGAAGAAGGUAAUCUCCUACAGAGGCUGCAUCACUCAGCUCUUUUUCUUGCACUUCCUUGGAGGAGGGGAGGGAUUACUCCUUGUUGUGAUGGCCUUUGACCGCUACAUCGCCAUCUGCCGGCCUCUGCACUGUUCAACUGUCAUGAACCCUAGAGCCUGCUAUGCAAUGAUGUUGGCUCUGUGGCUUGGGGGUUUUGUCCACUCCAUUAUCCAGGUGGUCCUCAUCCUCCGCUUGCCUUUUUGUGGCCCAAACCAGCUGGACAACUUCUUCUGUGAUGUCCGACAGGUCAUCAAGCUGGCUUGCACCGACAUGUUUGUGGUGGAGCUUCUGAUGGUCUUCAACAGUGGCCUGAUGACACUCCUGUGCUUUCUGGGGCUUCUGGCUUCCUAUGCAGUCAUCCUCUGCCAUGUUCGUAGGGCAGCUUCUGAAGGGAAGAACAAGGCCAUGUCCAUGUGCACCACUCGUGUCAUUAUUAUACUUCUUAUGUUUGGACCUGCUAUCUUCAUCUACAUGUGCCCUUUCAGGGCCUUACCAGCUGACAAGAUGGUUUCUCUCUUUCACACAGUGAUCUUUCCAUUGAUGAAUCCUAUGAUUUAUACCCUUCGCAACCAGGAAGUGAAAACUUCCAUGAAGAGGUUAUUGAGUCGACAUGUAGUCUGUCAAGUGGAUUUUAUAAUAAGAAACUGAGAAGGAGGAAUUCUGGCUGGAAUUCA